GGAGCCCUGCGUGCCAGGGAGGGGGCCGGCCGGGCAGGCGGCGGGCGGCGCUCGGAGCGGGCUCCGCGGCUUGCAAGGCGCCUGCGACUCGGUCCCAGGUCGGCGGGCGGCGCACGGCGGGCUCGCGCGGGGGCCCCGGCGCGCCGGGCGGCGCAGUACGCAGCGCGCGGACCCACGCCACGGCCAGGAGCCCAGAGCAGCGCGGCCACACUGCCCAGGGGUCGGCCCUCGGCCCCGGCGCUCGGAGCGCGGCGGCUGCCUGGGCUUUAAUGGCUGCUCCGCGGAGCAGCGCCUAGGGCUGGAAGGCGGCUGCGGCUCAGGAAGUCACCCGAGCAAGCCUCCUUCGGGGCCGGCCGCACCCGCCGCGGCGCGCUCCAUGGGGGCGCGCUCCCCCCGGGCGGCCCGCUGACCCGGGACGCCGGGGCCCGCUCGCUCGCCGGCCGCGCGUCCCGGCCAUGAACUGAGCCCGCGGGCCAGCCCCGCGCCUGCUCCGCCCGCGCCUUUCUUCUCGCGCCUCCUCCGCCCGCCGCCGGCGGGCCCGGCUCCCCGGGGGCUGCGGCGCCCCGGGCUCGGCGGCCCGCGGGCCCCGGGGCGCGGGGCGGCGGCGGCGGGGGGCGCGCGGCUCCGGGCGCGGCGCCUGCACCAUGAACUACCAGCAGCAGCUGGCCAACUCGGCUGCCAUCCGGGCCGAGAUCCAGCGCUUCGAGUCGGUCCACCCCAACAUCUACUCCAUCUACGAGCUGCUGGAGCGCGUGGAGGAGCCGGUGCUGCAGAACCAGAUCCGGGAGCACGUCAUCGCCAUCGAAGAUGCCUUCGUGAACAGCCAGGAAUGGACGCUGAGUCGAUCUGUCCCGGAGCUCAAAGUGGGAAUUGUGGGUAACUUGGCCAGCGGCAAGUCUGCCCUGGUGCACCGGUACCUGACGGGCACAUAUGUCCAGGAGGAGUCUCCGGAAGGUGGCAGGUUCAAGAAAGAGAUUGUCGUUGAUGGACAGAGCUAUCUGCUGCUGAUCAGAGAUGAAGGGGGCCCCCCGGAGGCGCAGUUUGCCAUGUGGGUGGACGCUGUUAUAUUUGUCUUCAGCUUGGAGGAUGAAAUAAGUUUCCAGACCGUUUACCACUACUACAGUCGAAUGGCCAACUAUCGGAACACGAGCGAGAUUCCUCUGGUUCUGGUGGGAACCCAGGAUGCCAUAAGUUCUGCUAACCCGAGGGUCAUCGAUGACGCCAGGGCGAGGAAGCUCUCCAACGACCUGAAACGGUGCACGUACUACGAGACGUGUGCUACAUACGGGCUGAAUGUGGAGAGGGUCUUCCAGGACGUUGCCCAGAAGAUUGUUGCCACAAGGAAGAAGCAGCAGCUGUCCAUAGGACCCUGCAAGUCGCUACCUAAUUCUCCCAGCCAUUCCUCCGUCUGUUCCGCGCAGGUGUCUGCCGUGCACAUCAGCCAGACAAGUAAUGGAGGUGGGAGUUUAAGCGACUAUUCCUCCUCCGUUCCAUCGACUCCCAGCACCAGCCAGAAGGAACUUCGGAUCGAUGUUCCUCCCACUGCCAACACGCCCACGCCCGUUCGCAAGCAGUCUAAGCGCCGGUCCAACCUGUUCACCUCUCGGAAAGGGAGCGACCCAGACAAAGAGAAGAAAGGCCUGGAGAGUCGUGCGGACAGCAUUGGGAGCGGCCGAGCCAUCCCAAUUAAACAGGGCAUGCUGUUGAAGCGAAGUGGCAAAUCGUUGAAUAAAGAGUGGAAAAAGAAAUAUGUCACCCUGUGUGACAAUGGCGUGCUGACCUAUCAUCCCAGUUUACAUGAUUACAUGCAGAAUGUUCAUGGUAAGGAGAUUGACCUUCUGAGAACCACUGUGAAAGUCCCAGGGAAGAGGCCACCCCGAGCCACGUCAGCCUGCGCACCCAUCUCCAGCCCUAAAACCAAUGGCCUAUCCAAGGACAUGAGCAGUUUACACAUCUCACCCAAUUCAGGGAAUGUCACUAGUGCAUCUGGGUCUCAGAUGGCAAGCGGCAUCAGCCUGGUCUCCUUCAACAGCCGACCCGACGGCAUGCACCAGCGCUCCUACUCAGUCUCCAGUGCCGACCAGUGGAGUGAGGCUACGGUCAUUGCAAACUCGGCCAUCAGCAGUGACACAGGGCUGGGUGACUCCGUAUGCUCCAGCCCCAGUAUCUCCAGCACCACCAGCCCCAAGCUCGACCCGCCCCCCUCCCCUCACGCCAACAGAAAGAAGCACCGAAGGAAGAAAAGCACUAGCAACUUCAAAGCCGACGGCCUGUCCGGCACUGCUGAAGAACAAGAAGAAAAUUUUGAGUUUAUCAUUGUGUCCCUCACUGGCCAAACAUGGCACUUUGAAGCCACGACGUAUGAGGAGCGGGACGCCUGGGUCCAAGCCAUCGAGAGCCAGAUCCUGGCCAGCCUGCAGUCGUGCGAGAGCAGCAAGAACAAGUCCCGGCUGACGAGCCAGAGCGAGGCCAUGGCCCUGCAGUCGAUCCGGAACAUGCGCGGGAACUCCCACUGUGUGGACUGCGAGACCCAGAAUCCCAACUGGGCCAGUUUGAACUUGGGAGCCCUCAUGUGCAUCGAAUGCUCAGGGAUCCACCGGAAUCUUGGCACCCACCUUUCCCGAGUCCGAUCUCUGGACCUGGAUGACUGGCCAGUCGAGCUCAUCAAGGUGAUGUCAUCCAUCGGGAACGAGCUAGCCAACAGCGUCUGGGAAGAGAGCAGCCAGGGGCGGACGAAACCAUCGGUAGACUCCACAAGGGAAGAGAAGGAACGGUGGAUCCGUGCCAAGUACGAGCAGAAGCUCUUCCUGGCCCCGCUGCCCUGCACGGAGCUGUCCCUGGGCCAGCACCUGCUGCGGGCCACCGCCGACGAGGACCUGCGGACGGCCAUCCUGCUGCUGGCACACGGCUCCCGGGACGAGGUGAACGAGACCUGCGGGGAGGGAGACGGCCGCACGGCGCUGCAUCUGGCCUGCCGCAAGGGGAAUGUGGUCCUGGCGCAGCUCCUGAUCUGGUACGGAGUGGACGUCACGGCCCGAGAUGCCCACGGGAACACAGCUCUGGCCUACGCCCGGCAGGCCUCCAGCCAGGAGUGCAUCGACGUGCUGCUGCAGUACGGCUGCCCCGACGAGCGCUUCGUGCUCAUGGCCACCCCUAACCUGUCCAGGAGAAACAAUAACCGGAACAACAGCAGUGGGAGGGUGCCCACCAUCAUCUGAGGAACAGCCGUGCCCGCCUGCUCGCCGCACCUGGGACGCGGCAGCCUCGCCGCAUUCUCGCUCAGAAGUCGCAGCACGUGAGUCCCGUCGCAUCCCCUCCCUCUUCCUGGUGGCCACCUCCCUCCCGCCCACCCACUCUCACCCCAAACAAAAUCACAAAACCUGGACAUCCCUCAAGGGGCGAAGAGGCGGCCGGGAGACUGCAGAAGUGGCUCCUUUUCAUAAACUCCCCUAAACCACACACAGGAGAGAGCGACGGGCCUCGGCCCUUUGAUGAUAGCACAUGGCGCAGGACCCUUGUCCUGGUGGCACAAGGGAUGGGGACGCGAGGGGGAGGGGAGGCGAGGAACAAGGAGAAGGGGCAACUUUCCUUAACUGGCAGUUGAGCACAUAGUACAUUUCCCCUCUACCAAACGGAACACUUGGAUUCCAUCUCUUCUCUGAGGAGCUCGACGGCAUAAAUCAGAAGCAAGCACAGAGUUUGUCAGGUUUGAAGCCCCUAUGAUGGUGUGUGUCAAAUCAGUUGUAGCUAAUCUGUCCAGGGAGAAUACUGGCUUCAUUACACUUGUACAGCCGAGUUCUUCCCGCAUUACUGCUGUUUAAUAGAACGUGAUUAGUCAUCGCCGAGAAGAAAGCAUAUUAGCCGAGGAGGUAGUCACGCGGCACGCGCCGGUGAUUGCCACGAUGUGAUUGCAAUACUCUUAGAAGCACCAUAUUAUCCCAGACAUGUUCUUUCAAGCCCUUGGAGCCCUCUCUAAAUUCACUGUCAUCAUUUAGUAUCUGUUUAAUUUUUCAGUCCAAAGAGAGGAAAUCAGUCGCUGAGUAUUAUUUGACUCCGGUCUCCUUGGUGCAAAAACAAAAUGGGAAAAAUAAAUAAGAAUAACUCAGAAACUCAAAAGGAAACCACAAAUUCAGCUAAUAAUAGCAUUUCGAGUAUAUUUCGUAAACUAAGGAAAUACACAAAAGGCUGUUUUUUCCGACUGUAAGAGAUAUUUGAUGUCCUUUUGCCGAGGUGGAUGUGUUAGUCUCAGGCCCUCCUGGACCACGUUGCCCAAGUCACACAGGCUUCUGUGUUAUGUAUUUAGAUAAGAUGUGUGAAAAUAUAUUUGAAUAAAAGAAGUUCAUAAAUAUGCAUUGAUUUUUGUACAGACAAAUGGCACCUCUCUUAAUUUAUAAAUUGAACUGGAUGUGAACUAAUAAUGUGCAACUAGUUGAGAUAAGAGGGUUACAGAUCAUUGUACAUGGAAAAUAUUCCCAGCAGUAAACACUUCCAUUAAUGUGAUCUACGGCUUUUGAAAAGGAGCAUCUCAGAAUAAGAUGGUGGUACAAUUUGCUUAUUAAAAUUGAGAAAGAAAAAAAAAGACACACUGGAGUAUAUUAGAAAGGAAAAAGAAGGAAUGUGGUCUCUCAUGAUUGAAAGCAUGAUUUAGAUCGGAUACGGCUUUUGCUAACCAAGGACCAAGGGACUCUGGCAAGAUGGGGUGGUUUUCCGAAUGCCAGACCGAGGUGCCUUACGAAGGCAGCUGCCAAUGGUUCUGUGGCACAGACUGGCUCCUGAGAACCCAGACGACCUUGACCUGGCAGCCCGGCCCUCCACGCUAGUACCUCGCCUGAUUUUCCAUCGUUGCGGUAUCCAGCCGCUUCAGACGUCCGCCGCCUUCAGUGGUGGUAGUCAAAUGUAGUCAACCAAACCACAGCAUCCCUUAGGUUAAAAGCAAACGGGGCAGCUUUGCCUAGAGCUCAUUGACAGUGUGAUGGGGGGAGAAGGGUUGUCACAAUGGAAGAUGAGGACACUAGACUCAUGUAGCACAGAAACAUGAAGCCACACGCACCGGCAGCCUCCGGGGUGUUCCUCGCUCUCUCGUAUGUUAAACCUUAUAUUUUAUAAGAGUUUUUCCUCUUAUUUCACUUUUUAAAAAAAAUUAAAGUAGGUGGGGAAAAAAAUAAAGCUUUACACAGAAUUUAUAUGUGGGUAAGUGUUUCAUGGAAAUUUCUAAUCUUAACGAAGCUAAGUGGAGCUCACUCGUAUCCAAAAGUAUAACAGGUGCAGAAGCCACAAGUCUGAGAACCUUGACGACAGUUCCAUCGUCCUGCCAUUUGAUUUUUCAGUCUGCGUUUCAUCACUGUGUAGCUAUUGUAAAUGUGAAUAGAAAAAAACAGGUCAUUGCCUAUUUUUGAAGAACGCGUUGGUGUUCGAGUCCACUAGACACACUCGCUCCACACAGCCUUCACCGUAGACUCUGUAGUGGACACAGAUAUAGCAUAAAUGAAAUUGUUAAAUUAUUUCAUUGUAGUUAAUUCCCACUAUAGGAAUGCUUUAUCAUAGUGAAGUUUCUUUUGAGAAGAAACGGAACUCCUUGAGGCUUCUCUUUGGGAUGUAUAUGAGCGUGUACAUAUUAUUCUAUGUGUUUAUAAUAUAAUAUUUUCCCAAAUGACUUCUUGUUUCACUUUGCCUUCCACAACCUGAAUGCCAGAUUGGUUUUUUCCCUUCCUGGCCCCCAGCACAAGCUGCCAUGACUCCCCCUCAGAAAACACAGCCCCUCCUCUACCAUUCUCAGUGAUGUCCAUCUGCUCCACUCCGCAGCCACUUUCUAGGGCCCAAGUUUUGGUAGCAGAAGGAAAGGCAGUUUUUGAGGGUCUUUCGAAAAAAAGAAGACGGGGCAGCUUUGCCCAGAGCUCGUUGGCAGUCUGUUUGUAUUUCAGUGUCUAACCAGAAGUCCUUUCUUUGCGGACCGCACUCUCGUUCCCACUUUCAAGCUAAUUACCACCAAGGCUGGGAGAGGCAAGGACUGGGGGCGGAGCUAGGAAUAACUCGUUUGAGAAGGGGGUGGAGUUUUCGUUGUUCAUUUCCAUGUUCAGUUCUGUGACGUGACGAUGACAGAUCACCACUGCAGGAUCCCCCUCACCUUUCCUGUUCAGAAUUAAAACUCUCCCUUGAUGAGAAACAGCCAGCUGAGGGAGGCCCACGAGCGGCCUGUGUAACCCCAUGGGUGAUCUGGACACAUCUGCACCCCCGCGUUCAGCUUCGCGGAGACUGAACUUGGCGGGGAGUGGAGGGGUGUGGUGCAGACCUGGCUGCAGCAGAAACACCCCGCAGGGACAGUACUCUGUGAUUCUGACCUCAGGUGCUGGGACGGGCAGAUGGUUUCCCCCGCCCAGCACCCCAGUCCUGGUCCCUGGUCCCUCUCUCUGUUUCAUCCCAGGAAAUGAGCAGCUCGAGGGUGAGCAAGUGACAAGUUCCUGAGUCACUGGCCCCAAAACCAGGUGCAGUGUCCUGUCUCCCAAGUGUGUGCACAAUGUAUAUAUGCACUGGAAAGGAGGGAGAAGGCAGCGGGUCACUCGCCAAUCGCAGGGUUCUCAGACACAGGAGAGAGCGGGAUCUUAAUGAAUUGCAUUUCCUGCAGAGCCUCUAGUGCACAGGCCAGUUCUCGGCAGUGGCUUUUCAGCACAAGGGCCUUGCAUUGAAGCUCCCUCUUCUGAGAUUUCACCCAGCCUGAUGAGGCCUGCAUGGUUCCGGCCUCGUCAUCCAGUGUAGAUACCAGUCUUCCUAUUUUUGUGACAUCUGCACAUUUGGGGUCAUUCCCUAUAUCUGCAUAGGAGCUAUUGCUAACCUUGUUAGGGAGAAACAUGGUCUAAUGAGAAAGACAGACCCCUAGGCUCAGCUGGCCCUGCCAUCCUUCCAGAGGAUUCCUCUGCAACUCUAGGCAAGCACCCAGCUUCCUGGGCUCUUUUUCCUCAUCUGUGAAACUUGCAGGGUGCAGUGAGGUUUCAAACCAGUGUGAUAAGUGUUGGCCUCACACCUGGCCCAGGGGAUGCUGGGAGAACAGGAGCACUUGUUAAUAACAGAAACACUGAUGGGACCGAAGCCAGUGCACACACCAGGAAACCUGCCCGUGGCUGACACUGUCCUCCAGCCUGCAUUCUGGGGAGGCUGUGAUGGGCACGUUUGCCAACCCCCCCCCCCCAGUAGAGCCCAGGACCCUCCUCUCUCAGCUUGCCAGUGCCCUGCCCUCCACAUGGCGGGGAACAGCAUCAAUGAGGUCCUUGCUCCCUGAGAGCCUCUCUGGAACCUGCCCACUUUUCUCAACAUGUAUAUUCUGCUUUGUAGUCUGAGGUUGAUUUUCUAGAGGCGAGGAAGGGGCUGAGUUCUGCCCUCGUGCUGUUCGCUGGUGCUGAUCAGGGCCAAGACGACCCUUCCCUCUCCCCCACAGCCUGUUGAGGUGCCGUUGACGUGGACAGCGCCCCUCCCUUAAGAUGCCCCCUUGCCGUUGCCAUGAGCCGCUGUGACUCACGCGUGCACUGGGCCUUGCUUGGUGCUCCCCUCCUCCUCCUGUCUGAGAUCGGAGCUUGCUGGAGAGCACCCCAGGUCGCCGUGCUUGGCUGCAGGCCCGUCCCUCUCUCCCCAUCCUCGGGUUCCCAGCGUGUUUUGUGCUUGAACUUGGUGGACUCAUCUUACCCCACAAGAGUGGCCUGCUCAACCUGCAGCCUCCAAUGUGCCGUAGGCGCUCUAGGUCCCCGUGGCGCCCAGGACACCAACUCUCCCUCCCUGCACUUAGGAUGUUCUGGAAAUGAGAGGAAAUCCACAUUCCUGCCCCAGGAGGUGGGAAGCCUGGCAACGAUGUAGCUUCCCCUGAGAUGCGGUAUGAUCAGGCCUCAGCAACUACUCAGGAGGCAAAGGUGUUUGGAAAGCAAACCCCAAACCUCCCGGCACGGCAUGUGCUCUGCUUCCGUCCCUCACCGCCUGCACAAGGUCGUUGAGACUUUUCUAGAACUCCCCGGGGUUGUAUUUAUGGCCUUCAAGCAAACAAAUUGAAAAGCAGUCAAGGAGGAGUUCAGAUAGAAAAGUGCUGGAGAUACACAUCUUUCCUUCAAAGGAAAUGUAAUUUAUUUCCAACCGCUGCCUCAGACGGGGGUUUCACAUGUUGUGAAGUCACAUCUUGAAUGACUGUCACCCUCAUCCUUCCCCAAAAAGCUAAAUAAGGGCCUUUGGCAUCAAUGCGUGCAUUCUCCACCUUUCCGCGGCUUGCGCUUGGAUUUCUGAGUGGCUUUCUUCAGGGAGCCCUUGUGGUCAUGUGUCUUUAAUGCUGCUCCCCAUGCCCCCAGGCCAGGCCAGCACGCUCAGGUGAUAGCGAGUGGGGCCAGGAGACCCCCCUGCCCUGCCCAGUGGACAGAUCUGCCCCAGCCCUGCUGUGGGGACGGGCCCUCUAUCAUUUAACCACAUACAUUAGGUUGCUUUUCAGCAAAAUGUCAGCUUUCCUCCCAUUAUGCAGGAGAGAGAAGGGGCGCAGGUGUAUCUCCUUAGAGUACACCUUGGAGCUGGAUCACUAAGAAACAGUCCUCAGACUGGUCCUUCCGACACAGGCAGAGAGUGAACUGGAUCGCUGGCCCCUGGGAUGCUGCGCUGUCUGUGAUUAGAGAGAAGUGGCCAGUGUCCCGUCUGUGAUUAGACAGAAACCCCUGUGGCAGACUCCUCCCCUCUCCAUGAAGAAAGAAAUAUUUACUUAGAUAUUACUGUUUCAAAACACAAACUUUAUUCCCCUUAGAGAAGAAAUACUGCCCUUAAAUAGACUGUUGAAAUAUUAAUGGCCCCCCCAUUUAAUCAGUGUGUCUGCGGCUUUCUUCGCGUCACAUGUCCGCAUUGGCAGGUGAUUCUGGAAAGGGAUUCUGGGAAACCAACAAGUCUUUUUUAAAUCUUUGAGUUGUAUGAGAAAGUAUUUAAGUUCACCAGUGUAGUAAACACCCACCCCAGAGCAGCGGUAAGCAAACCUAAAUCUGAAAACCCAUUCUUACUGUCUUUCACCAUGAGAUGCUGGUUUUGGUGUAAAAUGACAGCACUUGGUUUGGGGUUUUGCACCUGUUGGGUAGAACUGUUCUUGUCUGAGGUCCUCACCCUCUACAGAUGGGCCUCAGGGCCUGGAGGUGGGCAGAUGGGGCCAGAGUGGCCAGCAGAGACUUGCAUGGGCUCUGAAAGCCCCAGAGCUCAGGCCUAAGGCUGCUAGGUGAGACCAGCAGGCAGCUGUGGCAUCCGACCUUGGGACGCCCAAGCUGGGCAGCCGCUCCAUGUGCCCCAAACAGGAUAUCCUCAUGAAUGUGAGGAGAGGCUGGCUCAGGGCUUGGUUUUCAUUUUGGCCUGGCACAGGGUACCUGUAGGGAGCACUCCCCCAACCUGAGGAUGGUGAAACCAUAUGAUAGAGACUCCUUGUCGAAGUCCACAUCGGACUGAUCUAGAAUGCCCCGUGGGGGGAUUGCAUGGCCUUUGCCUUGAGAUGCAGGUGAAAGAAAGGAACCAAACAAGGCAUGAGUGUGUUGGGGAAUCUUCCCAGUGGAGCAAACCCCCUUAACACACCAGCUGUUGGGAACAGCUGCCCCUAAAUCCAAUUAAACCCUCAUCUCCCUGGUGCUGAACAGUCUACACUGGCCCAGGAAGCUAACGUCUGAGCCGCUUGGAGAGCUUUGGUAAACAGAAGACACUGGAAGCCCACUCGGUCAGCAGCUGGGCAUGAGGAUGUCAGGGGCCUUUGGACUUGAGGAAGGACAGUCCAGGUGCAUGGAAUCCUAAUGGGCCUCAUGCAGACACUGGAAGCAGCCCAGCCCCCUGCCCAAUACCACAGCCCUGGGGUGUCCCCUGACAUUCCUGGAGGUCCCUGGGCAAAUGCAUUUCCUGCCUGGGUUCUCAGGGUAGGAGAACAGAGAAGGCUCCAAGGGUGUUGGGAGUGAGCCAGGGGCUGGUCUGGGGAGUGGGUCUCACGCACUGCUCAGGUUGGCACGAGGGACCUCCCCCAUCCCAACCCAGCCCCAAGGGUCCCAGCAGGGCUCUCAGCAUGGCUGUUUUGAGGGUACACAGGUGGCUGGAGAGGGGUGGGGCAGUUGCAUGGUGGGUGGCAAAGUGUGCAUUUAGAAGCUGCUUCGUGGCGUUAAGAACGGGGGGAGAGGGACCAGCACUGUAACGUUAGAAAUAAUUCCUUCUUGCAGACUUGAAAAGCAUCAGUUUCCCUCCCACGGCUGGGUUUUUGUGUCUGAAAUACAUCUAAUUCUCCAGACUGCAGCCCCUCUCAGCCCCGAGCACCUGAGCGCUGGGGAGGCCCUUAUUGAGCUCAGCCUGGAGAGGGGAGGGUCGCACGGGUCCCGGGGGCAGGUCUCCUGCACUGGCUCUUCCCUUCUGCCAGCUUGGAAUUUGGUUCUCAUCUUGCCACAGGGGUGCGUUUCCUAAAGGGCAGCCGGAGCAGCUCAAAGGUGACAACUGAGAUGCAUUUCUAGGCAGGGGCAGGGAAGGCCAACCCACCUUGCAGCCAGUUUUCUGUUUCUGUAAAUAGCAGUGUAUAGAGAUGGAAGGGCAGCGUGGGUGUAUCCACAGAUGGGUUUAGGUUUUUUUUUUGGAUGUUUUCUAUUACCUCAUUCAGCAACUUUAUGUUUCACAAUGACUCAAUGAUGCUUUAUUUAUAUUGUUUGUACUGUAAUUAAAACCAUUGACAGACAUUUCACUUUGCUUGUUAUUUCAUAUGAUCUUGUUUUGAUUAAAUAUGCCAGUUUGUAUUUUCCUGCCUUGGGAUUUUUUUGUGUCCGCUGUACAGUAUUCUAAGGGAAAAAGAAAAAGAAAGAUGUGUAAAGUAACAGAGAGAGGUGGCUAUGGUGUAGAGACCUCUUUCUAAUAAAGAAAUGAAAAUAUGUCUA